CAAUCACCCCACCAUCCUCCCCCCAACCAGCCGUCCACAGCCGUCGUCGCUGCCCCUCCCCUGUAUUCCCAGUGCGCUGCCCUUGCACACUUCCCCAGCUCGUUUAUUAUGGAACUCCUCCGUGUGGCAUCCUAAGCUCCCAACGCCCUCCCCACUGUAAGCCCCCUUCUCAAAGCCAGAACCAUUCACUGACUGGCGCAGUGAACACGUCUUCUAUGUCACUAAGCAUCCGGCAUCAGCGGCAAAGCCCUUCUGCCCAUCCCCGCAAUAGAAUUUGGGGCUCGGGCUGCAGAUCUCAGUGCCCAUGCCAGGUGAACCUGGCCCUUCCACAGGCACUGAGCCCUCCAAGUGACACUCUCUCACACACACACAUCCCCAACAUUAAUCAGAGACCCCUACCAAAGUAGACUUCUAGGACCCCAGGGCCACCACAGCAUUGCCCAUGGGGGGGCCCAGAUCCUCCUCACCAGCCAUGUAGACCUCAGUCCCCUUCACAUCAUCCCAGGCCCUCUUCAUCUUCCAGAAACAGCCACCCAUCAGUCCAGGACUCUCAUCAGCUCAGGUACCCCCACAUUGGCCUAGGUGUUCCACAUCAGCCCCCAUAUAGACCCCAGACACACCCAUGGACCUCUGGUGCCUUCUGCUAAGACCUCCUCUUUACCCUCAUCCCUGAUAAACUUAGCAUCUCCUCCCACAGACCUCAGCCCAGGACCCUGGAGGAUGCUGAGGGGCUACAGCCCCCCUCCCUAGAGUCUCCAGGGUGAGCUGCCAUGAGCACCUGAGAGAGUAUAAGGUCUGAGGCCCCAGGGCAAAGGGAUUUCUUGAACCUGUGGAGCUUCAAAAUAGGCCCUUUUUUCUUAUUCAAAACUACAUAUAUAAAAGUGUGAAUACAACAUAAGAGAGCAUUUUUGCCUGUGGCCUUGGCAGGGAAGACCAAGCUGGUAGUUUCCCAAUCAGGGUGCAGGUGGCCGGGUACGCUGACUCGAAGAUGGCUGGCUGGGCACAGUCCCCGUGAGUUGCCUUUCUGCCACCCUGCACCUCUCCUUUCUCCUGGAUUGUAAAACCAGAUGCACGAGAACUGCAGAGUGUAUGAAAAAUGCAGCAGAGGAUGAAGAGGGAAAAAUCCCAUGGAAUCCCUCCUUUUCACUUGUCAUAAGCAUUUCCCAUAUGGUCAAAAAUCCUUCCUAAAGAUGUCUUGUUUUGUUUUGUUUUUCCAUGUUGAUGAAGGUCACAUGGGAGCCCGACACCAUUUGGAGGAGAUUCAGAGAAGUAUGAACAGCACAAAGCACUUGGCCGCCCCCCAUGGGCGUCUUCCCAGGACUCCCUUUCUAUGACACUCACGCAUCAUCCUGCAUCCCACGUUCCCUGUGCCUCAUGUCAUCUGUACAUCAUGUGUCUACUCCCCGUGGUCAUGUCAUAGUGUUGUGUACUGGGCACGGUUGAAUACUCCCAUCACAUGAUGGGGGAGGUAGUUGAUCCCACCACGUUCAACUGUUGGGCACUUUUGUAGUGAAUCUUGGUGCCUGAAUCUCGCAUCUUGCACGCAGUCUACCAAGUGUUCUUGAUAUAUAAAUGGCCACAGUGCUUUCCAGAAAGGUCGUGCCAAUUUAUAUUCUCACCAGCGGAUCAGUCCAGAGUACAAUUGUUAAAGACAAACAAACGAAACCUCCCUGCUUAUUUUUAUUUUUACAACUUUUAAUGUUUUCUUCAGUUAUAUGUUCACCAUAGUCGGCUUGGAAAAUGUACAAAAGGCCCCUGAUUGCUGAUUCUGUCCGCCUGCCACACCGGCUCUGUCCGGAGCCACUGGGACUCGGGAUCCAGUCCACACACACCCCUCAGAGGGGCACUGUGGCCAGAGAAAUGCUUCCACGGCCCAAAGCCCCUGCCUCCCCCAGACGCCCCCAGACCCCAACCCCGAGUGAGCAGGACGCAGACCCUGGGCCAGCAAGCCCCAGGGACACCGAAGCCCAGCGUCUGCGCUUCCGGCAGUUCCAGUACCACGUGGCGAGCGGGCCGCACCUCGCGCUGGGCCAGCUCUGGACGCUGUGCCGCCAGUGGCUGAGGCCCGAGGCGCGCUCCAAGGAGCAGAUGCUGGAGCUGCUGGUGCUGGAGCAGUUCCUGGGCGCGCUGCCCAGCAAGAUGCGGACCUGGGUGCAGUCACAGGGCCCCCGAAGCUGCAGGGAGGCCGCCAGCCUGGUGGAGGACCUCACACAGAUGUGCCAGCAGGAAGUUCUGGUAUCUCUGGACUCGGUCGAACCCCAGGACUGGAGUUUCGGUGAGGAGGAAGAUGGGAAGAGUCCAAGGUCCCAGAAAGAACCAUCGCAGGCGUCUGAGCUGAUUCUGGAUGCAGUGGCAGCAGCCCCAGCACUCCCCGAGGAAAGUGAGUGGCUGGAGACUACCCAGCUCCAGCAGAGUCUGCACACCAGGGCGGAGGCCGAAGCGCCCCGCGCCCCUGGCUUGCUGGGGUCCCGGGCCCGCUUGCCUCUGAAGCCGAGUAUCUGGGACGAGCCUGAGGACCUUCUCGCAGGGCCCUCCUCAGACCUGCGGGCAGAAGGGACUGUGAUCUCGAGCCCCAAGGGUCCAAGUGCUCAGAGAAUCAGUCCCCGAAGGAGAAACAGGAACACUGACCAGAGCGGCCGCCACCAGCCAUCCCUCAAGCACACCAAAGGUGGUACCCAAGAGGCUGUUGCAGGCAUCUCGGUAGUGCCGCGUGGGCCCCGAGGUGGGCGGCCCUUCCAGUGUGCCGACUGUGGGAUGGUCUUCACCUGGGUCACCCACUUCAUCGAGCACCAGAAGACCCAUCGCGAGGAAGGGCCCUUUCCGUGCCCCGAGUGUGGCAAGGUCUUCCUGCACAACUCCGUCCUCACUGAGCAUGGCAAGAUCCACCUGCUGGAGCCACCGAGGAAGAAAGCCCCCCGGAGCAAGGGCCCCCGGGAGUCCGUCCCACCCAGGGAUGGAGCCCAGGGCCCAGUGGCCCCUCGCAGCCCCAAAAGACCCUUCCAGUGUAGCGUCUGCGGGAAGGCCUUCCCCUGGAUGGUCCACCUCAUUGACCACCAGAAGCUCCACACGGCCCACGGCCACAUGUGAAUGGCCAGCCUCGGGCCUCGGCCACCCGGCCCUGAGUCCCUGGGGGGAGCUGAUGGGCCCCAGAAGAUGGGGGACAUCCCCCAGCCCCACCAACCCCUGGCCACCUUGGGACUCCUCUUGAAGGACACAAGCUGUUUCUCGGAAGACCCUGGACACCUGCUCCGAAGCCAAGCACGGGAUGGGGCUUCCCAGGGUCUCAGCUGAGAAGCAGCAGUUCCACAGCACAGCCUGGUCAGUCCUGCGCACUAUAGUUUUGCAAGUGGCUUGAAGAGGAGUUUCAUUCGCGUCCCAUCUUUCAGAAGCCUUGUCCAGGUCUCCCUGUUAGCACCUGACUCAGCGGCAGCUUCUGCCGCUGGGUUUUCAUUUCACUGUGGAUAUCCCUGAGGCCAUGAGGGUGGGAGCCGGCCUGGGCAGCUCCAACUCCAGAGAAGGGUACAGCUGACCCCGGCUGCCCUCCUGCCAGCUUAGCCCCCUUGGAACCUAACAGAUAAACAGGGUUUUGUUUUUUUCCUUUUUUGGGUAAAGUACAUGCAACAUAAAAUUUACCAUUUCAGUCAUUAAAAAUGAACAGUUCAGUGGCAUUAAGCACAUUCACAACACUGUGCAACUACCAGCACUCUCUAGCUCCAAAGAUGUUUUCGUCUUGCCCAGAAAGAGAGCCCACAGUCCUCAGCACGCCUUCGCCAUUCCUGCCCGCCCUGACAACCAGAAUCUGCUUCCUGUCUCUGAGGAUUUCAGGCGCAGUCUUUAGGCCUGACCAAAACUGACCUGCCUGUAUUUUGUUUGACUUACAGAAGGAUUUUUUUUUUAGAUAGAUGCCAACAUUUGUUUAAACCAUAAAAAUCUGGCUUUCUGGUCUGCCAGGAAGGAUCAGAUGGUCUCCAAAGAGUGGGCCCGCCUCUCCUGCUAGGCUGGAGCAGAGUGUGGGCAGGCGGUGACGUCACAGCGGGGAGCCAGCCUCGGACUCGGCUUCUCACCCGUCCCCAACUCAUUGUUGUCGGACACUCGUCCCCUUUCAAGCAAAAGCCUUAAAAGUUUUUGCCUUUUUCUUUUUCUCCUCCCGACUUCACUUGGAAACACAGUGUUGGGCUGACUGUGAAUCCGCACAGGCAGAGACAUUUUUCCAAGUCGCCUUCUAAAUCAAAAGCCUUUGGACUUACCCACGUCACAUCCGCCUGCUGCUGCUUCUCAACCAAGCUGCCCCCACUCUCGGCCUCUGUCCCCGAUGGCCCUCUCGGGCUGUGCAGGUCCCACGGACCCACCGCUGCCUUCACUUCAUCCUCGCUGCCGCGCUUGCCUUCUCACGCUUGCCUUCUCGGAGCGCCCCCUAACCGCGCCUCCGGACCUUGCUUCCCGGCUCCCUCAGGCAUCCCCAGCUUUUCCCUGCAGUCCCCACUGGGGGCUCCUGGCUCUAUCCUAUGCCUUAAUUGCUGGUGGGCUCCAGCUCCCCUCCUGGCACCUUCUCUCUCAUCCUGCAAAGGAGGAGCUUCUUCUACAGAGCUCAGGAUGGAGGGUGGGGUCUUGGCCCCGCAGUCAGCCCAUUACUCUCGGAAGCCCCCCUGAGCCUUCUCUCAGGCGCAGAUUGAUCGUCUCAGACAACGGGAUGUGUAGAGAUAGCUCUCCCGAGUGCCCCCACUUGUUGGGAGCCAGGGGCUCAUUCCAUGCUGUUUCCAUCUCGGUCUCCACCUGCUGGAGGCACAAUCACAGCUCAGUUUGUUGGUGCCAGAGUUGCACAAGAAAGUGGGUGCCAUUGAACACGAGGCAUCAGUCAGGCUCCAGCCUACCUGGGCUGGCCCCAGAGACAUCCAUCUGGUGUCCCUCAGUUCUCCAAUUGAGUUUGUCCAAAUAACUCAUCUUCCCUUGUGCAAAAACAAAAAACAACAACAAAGAAAACAACGCAAACUGCCUCCCCUCUGGGGUUCCCACUCCCCUCAGAGGGACCACCACCUUCCAAGGCCCCACAAGGAUUUUUGAUUGCCCUGGGAACCCAGCUCCCAAUCCCUCUCAGUUCUCUUUUCUCCUCUGCACCAUCAGCCCCAGGCUCUCUCCCCAUUUCUUGAAUGCCUGCAGCUGCCUCUAAGCAAACUCUGCCUCCAGCCCGUUCCCUCUGCCCCAUCCCCAUCCUGCAGCCAACAGGGUCCCUCUAAAAUGCAGACACUGAAAAGACAAAGCCCAGCAGGGUAGCUCUAUAGUGUCCUUUGUGGCCCUGCUGCCUCCACAGCCCCCAGCACUGGGAUGGUGGAGGCUGGUGUCCUUAACUCACUGUGUCUCCACCUGACUCCACACUGCCUCUCACCCUGGCCUCCUCCUGUGCCUAGAACAGUCUCCACUGCCAUACUUGACCACACCCAGCAUACAACAGGUCCUACAGAGUGAAGGGAUGAGUGACUCAAUGAGUGAGGGGAAGUCCCUGUGGAGACACCGGGACACCAUUGUGGGCUGCAGUUUCCA